GUGGACGGGCCGGAGGCGGCGUCGCUCGCGCCGCUGCGUGCGGUGUGGUGCGAGGCGGGUGCGCCGGGCGGCCGCGGCGCGGCGGGACCAUGGAGCUCAGAGCGCAGCCCCGGCGCCGGCGGCGGGACCGCGGACCGGUGAGUGAGGGCUGCGGUCGCCCCGGCUCUCCGCUGUAGGCUGCUGUGGCCCUCUCGGCUCCGGGCCGGGCGGCUGUCGGGGGAGGGGCGGCCCCACGGCGAACUGAAGUUGCUGCAUCGCCGCGCGCUCCGGCCGGGCGGCGGGGCCCACUGCGGGCUGCGGCGCCGCCUCGCGCCUAUCCCUGCAGCCCGGCCGCAUUCUCCCGGCCGGCUCCCGCGCUGGCAGGGGCUUCUCGCCGUCACGGCGCGGCCAGGCGGCCCUUCUCUCCCGCGCCUCCGGGCCUCCGGCCCUUUGCCGUCCGGUGCGCGCUCCCUGGACUCGGGACAGCCACCCGCCCUCCCCGCCUUUUAGUUUUGAUUGCUGUUAACUACUACUGAUAACUGAGCCAAAGUGGUGAUGCUACUUGAGGGGAAUUUCUGCAACCCAUAGUCAACGAUUACAUGAUUGUGAACCAUGCCUUUAGUGAAGAGGAACAUUGAGCCCCGGCACUUGUGCCGGGGAGCUCUGCCUGAAGGGAUUACCAGCGAACUUGAAUGUGUAACCAAUAGUACUCUUGCCGCUAUCAUACGCCAGCUGAGCAGUCUGAGCAAACAUGCUGAAGACAUAUUUGGUGAGUUGUUUAAUGAGGCUAACAACUUCUACAUCAGAGCAAAUUCUCUUCAAGACAGAAUUGAUCGCCUUGCUGUCAAAGUCACCCAGCUGGAUUCAACAGUGGAAGAGGUCUCACUACAGGAUAUCAACAUGAAAAAAGCUUUCAAAAGUUCCACAGUCCAAGACCAGCAAGUGGUUUCAAAGAACAGCAUUCCUAAUCCUGUUGCUGAUAUUUACAACCAGAGUGAUAAGCCACCGCCUCUGAACAUCCUGACACCAUACAGAGAUGACAAGAAGGAUGGGCUGAAGUUCUAUACUGAUCCUUCCUAUUUCUUUGACCUCUGGAAAGAAAAAAUGCUACAGGACACAGAAGACAAAAGGAAAGAGAAAAGGCGUCAAAAGGAGCAAAAGCGUAUAGAUGGCACCACCCGUGAGGUGAAAAAGGUUAGAAAAGCCAGAAACAGGCGCCAGGAGUGGAAUAUGAUGGCAUAUGACAAAGAGCUUAGACCCGACAACAGGUUGUCUCAGAGUGUGUACCAUGGAGCGUCUUCCGAGGGAUCCCUGUCCCCAGAUACUAGGUCACAUGCAUCGGACGUUACGGAUUACUCUUACCCGGCUACUCCCAACCAUUCUCUGCACCCCCAGCCUGUGACCCCUUCCUAUGCAGCUGGUGACGUGCCACCACACGGGCCUGCAAGCCAGGCUGCGGAGCAUGAGUACCGGCCCCCAUCUGCCUCGGCGAGGCACAUGGCCCUCAACAGACCUCAGCAGCCGCCCCCCCCGCCUCCCCCUCAGGCCCCAGAGGGGUCCCAGGCCUCUGCACCGAUGGCUCCAGCAGACUACGGGAUGCUCCCAGCGCAGAUAAUUGAGUAUUACAACCCAUCCGGACCACCUCCUCCGCCACCUCCUCCUGUGAUUCCCUCAGCACAAACUGCCUUCGUCAGCCCUCUCCAGAUGCCCAUGCAGCCCCCGUUCCCUGCAUCAGCCAGCUCCACGCACGCAGCUCCUCCUCACCCACCCUCCACCGGGCUCCUGGUCACAGCCCCGCCACCCCCGGGCCCACCACCUCCCCCGCCAGGCCCUCCUGGUCCCGGGUCUUCUCUUUCGUCCUCCCCAAUGCAUGGCCCCCCAGUAGCUGAGGCGAAGCGGCAAGAGCCUGCACAGCCACCAAUCAGUGAUGCUCGAAGCGACCUCCUCGCUGCUAUUCGAAUGGGAAUUCAACUGAAAAAGGUGCAGGAGCAGCGGGAGCAGGAGGCCAAGCGGGAGCCAGUGGGGAAUGACGUGGCCACGAUCCUGUCCCGGCGCAUUGCCGUGGAGUACAGCGACUCUGACGACGACUCAGAGUUCGACGAGAACGACUGGUCCGACUGAGCAAAGGCCGGCGGAGAGGCCGCGUGUGGGAGCGUGUUGAAGAUUUUAAGUGGUCUCUACACCCAAAUAGUGGUAUUCUAAUCCCGUAGCAUAGCACCUUUUGUAUAAACAAUGUGAUAUUGCUUCUGCACAUCCAAAAAUUCUGGGUCUUUUCAGUAUUUACUGUGUAAUACUUAAGUGCCACUAAACAUAGCAAAUUGUGCUGCACAUGAGGAAAUAGGCUGUCACUAUCACAUUGUCCUGAAAACAGCAUCUGCUUUCCUCUUGGCCAUGAGAGUAUUUAGUGCAGUUUGGGUUUACUCUUACUGAUCAAUAUAACUCUGCAGACUUGCUGUGUGUUUGUGAAGCUGCCUGGUGUUAGGUCUCUGCAAGACUAAUGACUAUGUCAGAGUGAUGUCUUCCAACCAGUAAGUGAUAUUGUUUCACCGCUUUGGUUUUUCCUUUUGUUUUUUUAAAGGAUGUGUUUCUGAAUAAGUUGGUUUUAGAGGGAAAGGUUCAACAAACAGGGAGAAUCCAGUGUUUCUGCUUUCAGUUUCUUGGCUUGGUAGCCUCUGAGUGAAUCUGAUGCUCUGCUGAAUAAUUUCAUUACCUCUGCACAUGCCUGUCAAAUAUGAAAUUGGAAGGGCCCUUUUCAGGCUGGGUUCCCUGUGGGCAUUUGCUUAGUAAAUGCCUGUUGAUGGUUUUUGCAAGAGAAUUCAGCAGCUCAACAGUAAUGAAAGUGAAGAACAGAGUCCAUUUUCCUUCCUGGGGCCAUUGGGGAUGACACUCAAGAUACUUGCCAGUCUCUCCAGUGUGGGCACCAGCCGGCCAGAACAGAUGCGAGCAGUCCAUGACUCUGGGAGCUACACCGCUGAGCUGGGCAGAGCUGCGGCACAGGGCCUGGGCUGCAAAGGAGCCCUGCUCCUUUAGUUUCCUGACACCUGUGUCCUGAGUGAGCCGCAGGAGUUCUUAGCUCCUCAGCGAGCAACAGAGAGCACUUUAGAUGGCACCUUUCACCACUUGGUCAGAAUUUUAAAAGCUUAGGUUUAGGUGAAAGUAGAUAUUGACAGCUAUUCACCUUUCACGGUGCUGGGGCCAGAUUAGGGAUCACUCCCGUGAGGAGGGCCUUCACCCUGUUCUAGAAGCACAUGGUUGUCCUCCUGUUGUUGGCACAUUAAAUGAUAAAAAGCACCUCAUGAGAUUCCCUUGAUCAGCCCUGCAGCUGUAGUACAGUGCUGUGCCCUCACCUCCACCCUUCCUGUUGUUCCCACGUGGGCAAUACCAGGGACCCAUGGGGAAACUCAAGAAUGACAGCUUCUAUAUUUUGUAAUUCUGGAUGAAAGAUAACUGUGUUGAACAAACAGGUGCUCCAGGCUUUGAUUAUAGAUACGACUUCAAAAAUAUGCUAAGACGCUUGACUUAUUAAGGACUUUAACCUACUCAACAGUAUUUCAUAUCCAUUGUGGUUAGUUACUCAGUUAUGUUGAGAAGAAUCUGGAGCUAAAAGCAGAGAUGUUUGAGGUGACGGUAGGAAUGUGAGCAGGAUGGUGAUGGGGGUUUUUGUUAAAAUGCAUCUGAGCAAGUCAGCCAGCCCCGAAGUCCCCUCAGUGUGUGUGUCUCGAGUGGCUACCUGUUGGGCUUGUGGGCAGUGAUUGUACAGAGCCUGUCCAUUGGGUGCAGUCAUGUAGAUCUGAAGCCCUGAAAAGCCUCAUGUCUGCAUCCCCUUUCCAAGGCUGCUUCCCUGGUGUGUCUGUUCUCUCCUCUGUCCCAGGUGCUGGGAGCGUCCUCUUCAGCGUCUUUUCCUAGAGCUGGUCACCACUAGGCUGUCACUAUAAAUUCCUUGAAUAUAAGUAACAGUUAUUAAUGAACUUCUAAAUUUCUAAUUUCUCUCUCUCUCUCUUUUUUUUUUUUUUGUUGUUGUUAAAAAGGGCCUACUACAUUGGCGCUAUUCUUAGGACUUCUGCAACUUUUAAAGUCUUACUUGUCUUUCUUGUUGCUUUUGUAUUAGGAGUUCCCCGUGUGGGUCUAGAACUCCCCUUUGGUAAUGCUUCUUUGUUUUUUUAUGGCCCUUCUGUUCUCAGGAUGGAGAGAACACAGAAGCUACUAUCCAUGUCAGGAUUUAUUCUAUUUAUAUCUUAUUACAAUAAAAUUAGUGGCACUUUAUUCAUAAAUAUUCAUGAGCCUGUUAAUUGUUAGUUGUCUUCCUGUAGCUGAAUCAACAAGUUAUUUUCAACUCAAUUUUAUGACUUGCGAAAAAGCUUUUGCCCUGUUGUGUACCAUAACAUUUAAAAGAAUGGAAAAUGACUGAAAUCCAAUUUAGAUUAUUUUUAGAGUAUUUUUCCAGCAAAUUCAAUUUAUUCUGAAAUUUAAAUCCAGAUCUUUUCUAAUAUGGUAUUACAAUGAAAAGAAUAAAGAGAAGAUUUGAAUUUUCAGUUUCAUUUUCAAAAACUAUUUACCAAAACAAAUGGAGAAGAAACAUCCAAAAGCACAUUUCAUUUCUCCAAACUUUGUGUUUUAAAUUAUAGUUAUAAAUUGUAAGGUAAUUUUAAAUUGUCCCUCGUAUUAUUUCUCCACGUCUGUUUUAGUUUAAUGUCUCCUAAGCUUUUCUCUCAUAGCGUAGACCUAGGGAAGGGAUGGGAAGAUUGCCCAGUCCCCGAUGGCUGCGCACACAGGAGGCGGCGGAGCACAAGGCAAGUGAGUUUGCACUGUCAGCCCCAGACCGUAAGCUUGGCUACACUGAUGUUUUUCUUUACUAAGGAUACUAUUCAAAAAUUAACAUUUUCAUCUCAGUAAGUUUUUAGAACAUCAAAAUGUUUUCUGAGCUCCAAGUGGCUAGGUUGUAAAAGUUUUAUAAUAAUUUGCAAUUAAAAUACAUGAUACAUAUUAAUCCAUUAAAGACUAGUGGGAAUGUAUCAGCCAGAGUAGCAAGUAAUUUUUGUUUUAUAAAUCAUAGUAUCUGUCAUCUUGCAGUAUUACCAAUGCUGUUGUAAAUUGAAUUUAAAGUGGUAUUAAAAAAAACUGUUAAACAAUUUUUAUCUGUUUGUAUAUCUUACUAUAGAUUAUGUACAAGUAACAUCUAAAUAAAAUUACACUUUUAACCCUAAGAGGUUUUGCUUAUUAAUAA